ACUCUCAUCAGAAGAGGAGAGGAGAAGAGAGGUUGGGACCAGUCUUCACCCCCUGGAAUGUCGCUGAUGAUAAAACCAUAAUGGUGGCAGCCCCAGCAUUUACAAAGAGGAGGGAUGCGGCACGGCCAUCUUGCUGAAAGCCCGAACUAAAGGAAGCUGUGUUUGGACAACAGGCACAAUUUGGGGUGGUGGCACAGGGCCACACACCUCCGGUUACCCCUUGGAUCAACCACAGGUAACCUAUGCAUGUGGCACAAAAUUCAAAAAAUACAAAAGGAUGUACGUUGAAAAGGUCUCACUCUGUUACCCAGGCUGGAGUGCAGUGGAGUGAUUAUAGCUUACUGCAGCCUUGACCUUCUGGGCUCAAGAGAUCCUCCCACCAUCACGAGGUCAGGAGAUCGAGACCAUCUUGGCUAAGAAGGUAGAGGAGCGCAUGUGAGCCAAGAUCCCUAGGCCUGAGCCGUCUAGGUGUGUCCCAGGAACUGCAGGAAACGGUUGGGUGAGUCAGUGGUGGGCAGCGAGGGUGAUAAGCCCCUUCGUGUCUUCGGGAUGCUCGACUCCGCGCUCUCCUCGCCGGCCGCCGCCGCCCAGCCUGCGCCCGCCGUCCCCCCAGUGCCUGGGCACCUGUUGGAGGCAGAGCCAGGGGUGCUGCAUGAGGGGCCGCAGGGGCGAUCGCAUGACCAUCAACAUCCAGGAGCACAUGGCCAUCAACGUGUGCCCCGGGCCCAUCCGGCCCAUCCGCCAGAUCUCUGACUACUUCCCCCGGGGACCAGGACCUGAAGGGGGCGGCGGGGGCGGCGGGGAGGCCCCCGCCCAUCUGGUCCCCCUGGCUCUGGCCCCCCCUGCAGCCCUCCUUGGGGCCACCACGCCUGAGGAUGGUGCGGAGGUGGACAGCUAUGACUCGGAUGAUGCCACCGCCCUAGGCACGCUGGAGUUUGACCUUCUCUACGACCGGGCCUCCUGCACUCUGCACUGUAGCAUCCUCAGGGCCAAGGGCCUCAAGCCCAUGGAUUUCAAUGGCCUCGCCGACCCCUACGUCAAGCUGCACUUGCUGCCUGGAGCCUGUAAGGCCAAUAAGCUAAAAACGAAGACUCAGAGGAACACACUGAAUCCCGUGUGGAAUGAGGACCUGACUUACAGCGGGAUCACAGAUGACGACAUCACGCACAAGGUGCUCAGGAUCGCCGUCUGUGAUGAGGACAAGCUGAGUCACAAUGAGUUUAUUGGGGAGAUCCGCGUGCCCCUCCGCCGCCUCAAGCCUUCGCAGAAGAAGCAUUUUAACAUCUGCCUCGAGCGCCAGGUCCCGCUGGCGUCCCCCUCUUCCAUGUCAGCGGCGCUGAGGGGCAUCUCCUGUUAUCUGAAGGAGUUGGAGCAGGCGGAGCAGGGGCAGGGGCUGCUGGAGGAGCGUGGCCGCAUCCUGCUGAGUCUCAGCUACAGCUCGCGGCGCCGGGGACUGCUGGUAGGCAUCUUGCGCUGCGCCCAUCUGGCUGCCAUGGACGUCAACGGUUACUCGGACCCCUACGUCAAGACGUACCUGAGGCCCGAUGUGGACAAGAAAUCCAAGCAUAAGACGUGUGUGAAGAAGAAGACUCUCAACCCAGAAUUUAACGAGGAGUUUUUCUACGAGAUAGAGCUCUCCACUCUGGCCACCAAGACCCUGGAAGUCACCGUCUGGGACUAUGACAUUGGCAAAUCCAAUGACUUCAUUGGUGGCGUGUCCCUGGGGCCAGGUGCCCGAGGCGAGGCUCGGAAGCACUGGAGUGACUGCCUGCAGCAGCCGGACGCAGCCCUGGAGCGCUGGCACACCCUGACCAGUGAGCUGCCCCCUGCGGCCGGGGCUCUGUCCUCAGCCUGAGUGGACAGCAGUGUCCCGGCACAGGCCCAUCGAGCCGGGUCCAGUACCCAACCUUCGCACGAGUGUGUUGCACGUUUACACAGGGUGGGCUGCCCCCACCCUGCACUACCUAUUUUUGUGAGUCUCCGUGACCCGGGUCUGUCUGCUCAUGAGGGGCUGCGGAGUUCUAUAUUCACAUAUGCAAACCUCCUGCCUGACUCGCUAGUCCCUGCAAAUAUGCAAACCCCCCAUCAUCUGCACACCCGGGCAGUGCUCAGAGCCCGGCCCCAGGCCCCCGCGCUCCUCACUCCUGCCUCUCCACGCUGCCCCGUCCCUCUCCCCCAACAGGGAGGAGGUCGGAUUAGGGGAGGUUCAGAGGAGGAGAAUGUCUCAAAAAAAAAGGACAAAAAACAAACCCAGAGCCACUCCUUUAAUACAGAAACUUCAUUGAAAAAACCUAGCCCUGUACAGCUGCCCUUUUAAAGAGGUGGCCAUUGCAGGGUCUCUGCCUCCCCAGCAGGUGGCAGAUGCUCCCGGCCACUCGUUUAAAUAACUGUCCCCUGGAGGGGGCCGGGGUUUGAAGGCAGGGCCCCUGCCACCCUCCUGGGGGACACCCGUGCAUGUUUACGCCUUUUCUGGUUGUGUCAGUGGCCGGAGCAUGGCAGCUGGGCAUCAAUAAACACCUCCGAGGAA